AGAAAAGAUGGCUGCUGUGCAAGUUGUCGGUUCGUGGCCUUCCGUGCAGCCGCGGGAGGCACCGCGGGAAGCAAUCCCUGAGCGAGGCAAUGGGUUUCGCCUCUUGUCUGCCAGGCUCUGCGCCCUGCGCCCGGAUGACAGCAGCUCCGCCCGCACCGAGAUCCACCUGCUCUUCGAUCAGCUCAUCUCCGAGAACUACAGCGAGGGCAGUGGCGUGGCCCCGGAGGACGUUAGUGCUCUUCUUGUCCAGGCUUGCCGACUGGUACCUCUUAAUCAGAAUCAUCUUGUCAGCAAAGUGAGCCAGCUUAUCCACCAUUUACUUAACAGAUUACAGGUAAUUGUUGAUGAACAGCACUUGGAUUUCCUGUUGGCAUAUACUAUUUCGGCUAUUCAUCAGUGUAGUUCCUGGACACACAGGGAAAUUCUUCAAGCCCUGGCAGCUCUGGUGUACUGCAAUGGCUCCAAAUGUCAAAAGUACCUCCCAGAGCUGCUAGGCAACACCGGACUCUUAAUGAAGUUGAGUGACUUGGCUCAGUCUGAUCCUGAAGUCAGGAGAGCUGCAGUACAUUGUAUGGCAAACUUAUGUCUCAGUGUGCCAGGACAGCCGUAUUUGGAGGAGCCCUACCAAAAUGUCUGUUUCCAAGCUUUUCUGACUAUUUUACAGUCUCCAAAAUCAUCUGAUAUGGAUGAUAUCACAUUUUGCAUGUUAUUGCAAAAUGCAUUAAAAGGUAUACAGUCACUUCUAAAUGGUGGGAGAAUGAAACUAACACAGACUGAUGAACUUGGAGCACUUUUAGCUGUGCUAAAGAAAUUCAUGUUUCACGGACUCCCUGGACUAAACAUAGAGAUGCCCACGGUGUUAUACCCAACUCCGCUUCCUCAGUAUGAUGGGCGAACACCUAUCAAACCACAGCAAUCAGAAUCCAGUGCUUCUCGACCAACUUUGAAUAAAAAGAAAAAAUCCAAAGUAAAACCAAAGAAAAUCCAGCAAGGAGAGGAGGAGGAAAAGGAAUCCAGUGGUGAAAUAGAGGCAGCCCCAGUCACUGGCACAGGCAGAGUGAACCUGCAUGAAGGGAACACUUGGUGUCCCUCCUCCCUGGGUGUCCAGAGUUUGCCUUUAGAUGGAAGUGGAGCUGCAGAAAAAGAUGGAGUCUCCUCAUCCUUCAGUUCUUCCAGUUGGAAAAGGGUCAGCAGUAGUGAGUCAGACUUUUCUGAUGCUGAAGGAGGCAUGCAGAGUAAAAUGAGGUCUUACCAAGCUAAAGUUCGCCAAGGAGCCUUAGUUUGUUUUCUUUCUACUAUAAAAUCGAUAGAAAAAAAAGUUCUUUAUGGCUACUGGUCAGCUUUUAUUCCUGAUACGCCUGAACUUGGCAGCCCACAGUCAGUGUCCUUGAUGACUCUUACAUUGAAAGACCCUUCUCCAAAGACACGUGCCUGUGCUCUGCAAGUUUUAUCUGCCAUCUUGGAAGGCUCAAAGCAGUUUCUUUCUGUUGCUGAAGAUACCAGUGACCACAGAAGGGCUUUUACCCCCUUCUCCGUAAUGAUCGCUUGCAGCAUUAGAGAGUUGCACAGAUGUCUUUUGUUAGCUUUGGUGGCGGAGUCAUCCUCACAGACCGUUACUCAGAUAAUUAAGUGCCUUGCAAAUUUAGUAUCAAAUGCACCUUAUGAUCGUCUAAAACUCAGCCUGCUGACCAAAGUCUGGAACCAGAUAAAGCCUUAUAUUCGCCACAAAGAUGUUAAUGUUCGUGUGUCAAGUCUCACACUCUUGGGAGCUAUAGUGUCCACCCACGCACCUUUACCUGAAGUCCAACUACUUCUGCAACAGCCAUGUUCUUCUGGACUCGGUAAUAGCAAUUCAGCAACCCCUCACCUCAGCCCUCCUGAUUGGUGGAAGAAAGCCCCUGCAGGACCCUCUCUGGAAGAAACGUCAGUUAGCUCACCUAAGGGGUCUUCAGAGCCCUGCUGGCUCAUUCGACUCUGCAUUUCCAUUGUCGUACUGCCCAAGGAGGAUUCCUGUUCAGGUAGCGAUGCUGGCUCUGCAGCAGGAAGCACCUACGAACCAUCCCCCAUGCGACUGGAGGCCUUACAGGUAUUGACUCUUCUGGCAAGGGGCUACUUUUCAAUGACUCAAGCCUACUUGAUGGAGCUUGGAGAGGUGAUUUGCAAGUGCAUGGGGGAAGCAGAUCCAUCCAUUCAGCUUCAUGGAGCAAAGCUUCUGGAAGAACUGGGCACAGGCUUAAUACAGCAGUAUAAACCAGACUCCACUGCAGCACCUGAUCAGAGAGCACCAGUCUUCUUGGUGGUGAUGUUCUGGACUAUGAUGCUGAACGGUCCUUUACCCAGAGCCCUGCAGAAUUCAGAACACCCAACUCUCCAGGCGAGCGCCUGUGAUGCCCUGUCUUCCAUCUUGCCAGAGGCCUUCAGCAAUCUGCCGAAUGACAGGCAGAUGCUGUGCAUCACAGUGCUGCUCGGGCUGAAUGACAGCAAGAAUCGCUUAGUGAAAGCUGCAACUUCACGGGCCCUGGGAGUCUAUGUGCUUUUUCCCUGUCUCAGACAGGAUGUCAUAUUUGUUGCAGACGCAGCAAAUGCAAUAUUGAUGUCACUUGAAGACAAGUCUCUGAAUGUUCGAGCCAAAGCAGCCUGGUCCCUGGGCAACCUGACAGACACUCUGAUUGUCAACAUGGAAACACCAGACCCAAGUUUCCAGGAAGAGUUCUCUGGUCUCCUGCUCUUGAAAAUGUUACGAUCAGCUAUAGAAGCAUCCAAGGAUAAAGACAAGGUAAAAAGCAAUGCAGUCCGGGCCCUUGGAAAUUUGCUUCAUUUUCUGCAACCCUCUCAUAUAGAAAAACCCACAUUUGCAGAAAUCAUUGAGGAGUCUAUCCAGGCCCUAAUUUCUACUGUUCUAACAGAAGCUGCCAUGAAAGUCCGAUGGAAUGCUUGUUAUGCAAUGGGAAAUGUAUUUAAAAAUCCUGCCCUUCCUUUAGGGACAGCCCCAUGGACCUCCCAGGCCUACAAUGCCCUGACAUCGGUCGUGACAUCAUGCAAGAACUUCAAAGUGCGCAUCAGAUCUGCAGCUGCCCUUUCCGUCCCGGGGAAGAGAGAGCAGUACGGGUCUGUUGACCAGUAUGCUCGGAUCUGGAAUGCAUUGGUCACCGCUUUACAGAAGAGUGAAGACACCAUAGACUUUUUGGAAUUCAAGUACUGUGUCAGCCUACGGACCCAAAUCUGCCAGGCACUGAUUCACCUCUUGAGCUUGGCCAGUGCCUCGGACCUCCCUUGUAUGAAAGAAACCCUUGAACUGAGUGGGAAUAUGGUCCAGUCCUAUAUUCUACAGUUUUUAAAAUCAGGAGCAGAGGGAGAUGACACUGGAGCACCCCACAGCCCACAGGAAAGAGACCAGAUGGUCAGAAUGGCCCUUAAACACAUGGGCAGCAUCCAGGCACCAACUGGAGACACAGCCAGAAGGGCCAUCAUGGGCUUUUUAGAAGAGAUCCUGGCCGUUUGUUUUGACUCAUCUGGAUCACAAGGGGCACUCCCAGGGUUAACAAAUCAGUGAAGAUCCCACCAUACUUUCUAGAUGUCGAAGGCGGCAGUAGGAAGACCUGAGCUUGAGCAUAAGAUCUGUGGGAUUUCAUCUUAGGGGCAGAAACAAUCCGUUCACUAUUUAUUUAGAAUGACUUAGCAGCCAUUUAAAUUUUCACAGAGGGCUCAACCACCUUUGGAGUGACUCCAUAGCACUGGCCAUGGUCAGGGUUGUUGGAACAUCUGACCUGUGCAUCCAGGAGCCGAGGAGUCAGGUUGUAAUACAGGCCAAGCAGACGGGCUUUGAGGGCAUUUAGUCUCAGAAAAAAAAAAUGUAGAAGGAUUUCGGAAUUAGAAUUUUGUGUAUUGUAUCUGUAGUUUUGUAAUAAACUAACGAAAAAUAGUGUGUCCACAAUCUCCUGUUGUUACCAAGUUGUAUUUCUAGCAAGCUGCAAGCAGAGCUGCAGUUCAGCCAGUUUGUCCUGGCCCAGCUGCACAGGAUGCGAGGAUGCUGACAGUGCCUCACAGCCGCACAGGACCGAGGAUGCUGACGGUGCCUCACAGCCACACAGGACGCGAGGAUGCUGACGGUGCCUCACAGCCACACAGGACGCGAGGAUGCUGACAGUGCCUCACAGCCACACAGGACGCGAGGAUGCUGACGGUGCCUCACAGCCGCACAGGACCGAGGAUGCUGACGGUGCCUCACAGCCACACAGGACGCGAGGAUGCUGACGGUGCCUCACAGCCGCACAGGACCGAGGAUGCUGACGGUGCCUCACAGCCACACAGGACGCGAGGAUGCUGACGGUGCCUCACAGCCACACAGGACGCGAGGAUGCUGACGGUGCCUCACAGCCGCACAGGACGCGAGGAUGCUGACGGUGCCUCACAGCCACACAGGACGCGAGGAUGCUGACAGUGCCUCACAGCCGCACAGGACGCGAGGAUGCUGACAGUGCCUCACAGCCGCACAGGACGCGAGGAUGCUGACAGUGCCUCACAGCCGCACAGGACGCGAGGAUGCUGACGGUGCCUCACAGCCGCACAGGACGCGAGGAUGCUGACAGUGCCUCACAGCCGCACAGGACGCGAGGAUGCUGACAGUGCCUCACAGCCGCACAGGACGCGAGGAUGCUGACAGUGCCUCACAGCCGCACAGGACGCGAGGAUGCUGACAGUGCCUCACAGCCGCACAGGACGCGAGGAUGCUGACAGUGCCUCACAGCCACACAGGACGCAAGGAUGCUGACGGUGCCUCACAGCUGAUGAGCUGCUGCUCCGAGCUUCUGGAGUGCCCGUGUUCCCCUGACCACCUUCCCUGCCACACCUCCCCACAAUCCAAUAACCAGAGUUAACUCCCAGCAAGCAGGGCCUUCUAACCUAGGCUACAACAUUGACUUCUACCUACAUUUCCUGAUGCUCUUUAGGAGAAUGUGAUCCCACACACUAAAUAUAUGGUUGUUUUGCCACCUUUUAAUUUGUGCCUUUAAGAAAAGAUCAUUUGGUUAGUUGGUUACAAAGAGGGGUUUCCAAUUAUAUUUUGAUAAUGCCCCACAAGUUAUGAAGGUAACUUCUACUGAAUAUAUAUAUUUAAAUUUUGCAUUUUUCUACUGAGCACCAACGAUUUAUUGGAAUUGAUUUCAAUUAGGAAUUUAGGGAUAUAUAAGAACCAAUUACAGUUGUCCAUACUUAUCUUUGAUGUGGGACAAUUAAGAAGUUACAAAAAAUGGGUGUUGGUGAUAUUUUAUCAUGGUUAUUUAGCUUAAAAUACACGUGUAAAGGCAGGUGUCUUCCAUUUUUCUCCUUUGCCUUUUAGCUGCUGUUUUCCUGCCUCUGACAUGUUGGCUGCUCAGAAACUGCUCUCUGGGCAGUGAUUGGGGAACAGGGUAUUCAAGUUCACUAAAGGCUCAAUUUUCCAUUGAUAGAAUAUCAGUGUCCACAGAAUUAAGACUGCAAGCACAGCAAAGACACCCAUAUUGAAUGUUCCCUUAAAUUGCUUUUAUUUGGAGACAAUUCUGAACAUGAAGUGUUAUAGAGGGCCCAGGAAACUAAGUUGAGCCCACCUGACCCUGUGAUGAAUCUUGGAACUUCCGUCUCUUGAAUACAUUCUUAGUAGUAGCUUCUUGGCAUUUUCAAAAAAGGAAAAAAAAAAUAUGGCAUAGACAGCUUAUUACUGUGAUUCUUUGAGUUUUCUCAGGUGAGUUUUUUGAUAAAAUAUUUGUGAAGUGGCCUCAUGGUUUCAUUUGAUGAUUCACUCUUAUCCUUUCCUUAUCUUGAAUAAAAUCCCAUUCAUUUUCUUUUUAAAACUUCAGCUUCUGUAAAGGUUUCCAGAUCCUGAUGUGGAUGUUAAUGUUCAUGUGCAGGAAAACAAUGAAGGCAUAGCACCUCUAGAAACUUCAGAAGGCAGUGGUACCUGCUGUGUCCCAACAGUAUGCUGAUUCUCUUCUCUGCAGCAUUGUGGGUGUACAUACACUAAAGGACAGAAGCUCCUCAUAUGCCUGGGCACGUGCCUCCAUAAAGCUGCUGUGGGGAAAGGAAGCCACUGACAAUAAAGACAACUUAAGCUGAUGAAAAUCAGCACACAGC